ACUAAGAGACGCGAGGGUCGCGAAGGGCACAACACUUGGCCUCUCGCUGGCCCUGCUCGCGGAUCCCGAGUAGAGAACGCAAGCACCCACGCCCGCCUGCAAGCUCCCGGGCGCCCCCGGCCUCUCCUGCUCGGCGGAACGAGGAUAACCCAGUAGAGCCGGACCCAGGGAUAUUAUUGAUAAUAAGGCCUCUGUAACCAUGGCUAGUUCUGACGUAAAACCAAAAUCAGUAAGUCAUGCCAAAAAAUGGUCAGAAGAGAUAGAAAAUCUGUACAGAUUUCAACAAGCAGGAUAUCGGGAUGAAACCGAAUAUAGACAAGUGAAACAAGUUUCUAUGGUAGAUCGUUGGCCGGAGACAGGAUAUGUGAAGAAACUUCAGAGAAGGGACAAUACGUUCUAUUACUACAACAAACAGAGGGAAUGUGAUGACAAAGAAGUCCACAAAGUGAAAAUUUAUGCUUACUAGCCUGUCUUCUUUGUAUUACUUGUCAAUUAUAUUUUAAGUAUUCAUCAUUUCCUUCUACAUCAUGUGUUUGUCAUUUGAUGAAAUAAUUCAAGAUGCAGUCUGCAGUUUAAUGUUUUGUGAAACACAAAAGCCAUGAGAAUUGGUAUCUGCUAAUCACCUUGUCCUGUUCUAAGAACUGGCUGCAGAUGCAUUAAAGUUGUACUUUCUUGGUCCUGC